AAACUAGUGGCGGGAGGCUGUGAGCUGAGCGGUGGGGUCUGCGUACGCCUGGAGUCCUUCCCCGCUGUGCUCAGCAUGGACCCUAUCCGGAGCUUCUGCGGGAAGCUGCGGUCUCUGGCCAGCACGCUGGACUGCGAGACGGCCCGGCUGCAGCGAGCGCUGGACGGAGAGGAAAGCGACUUUGAAGAUUAUCCAAUGAGAAUUUUAUAUGACCUUCAUUCAGAAGUUCAGACUCUAAAGGAUGAUGUUAAUAUUCUUCUUGAUAAAGCAAGAUUGGAAAAUCAAGAAGGCAUUGAUUUCAUAAAGGCAACAAAAGUACUAAUGGAAAAAAAUUCAAUGGAUAUUAUGAAAAUAAGAGAGUAUUUCCAGAAGUAUGGAUAUAGUCCACGUGUCAAGAAAAAUUCAGUACACGAGCAAGAAGCCAUUAACUCUGACCCAGAGUUGUCUAAUUGUGAAAAUUUUCAGAAGACUGAUGUGAAAGAUGAUCUGUCUGAUCCUCCUGUUGCAAGCAGUUGUAUUUCUGAGAAGUCUCCACGUAGUCCACAACUUUCAGAUUUUGGACUUGAGCGGUACAUCGUAUCCCAAGUUCUACCAAACCCUCCACAGGCAGUGAACAACUAUAAGGAAGAGCCCGUAAUUGUAACCCCACCUACCAAACAAUCACUAGUAAAAGUACUAAAAACUCCAAAAUGUGCACUAAAAAUGGAUGAUUUUGAGUGUGUAACUCCUAAAUUAGAACACUUUGGUAUCUCUGAAUAUACUAUGUGUUUAAAUGAAGAUUACACAAUGGGACUUAAAAAUGCGAGGAAUAAUAAAAGUGAGGAGGCCAUAGAUACAGAAUCCAGGCUCAAUGAUAAUGUUUUUGCCACUCCCAGCCCCAUCAUCCAGCAGUUGGAAAAAAGUGAUGCCGAAUAUACCAACUCUCCUUUGGUACCUACAUUCUGUACUCCUGGUUUGAAAAUUCCAUCUACAAAGAACAGCAUAGCUUUGGUAUCCACAAAUUACCCAUUAUCAAAAACAAAUAGUUCAUCAAAUGAUUUGGAAGUUGAAGAUCGUACUUCGUUGGUUUUAAAUUCAGACACAUGCUUUGAGAAUUUAACAGAUCCCUCUUCACCUACGAUUUCUUCUUAUGAGAAUCUGCUCAGAACACCUACACCUCCGGAAGUAACUAAAAUUCCAGAAGAUAUUCUCCAGCUUUUAUCAAAAUACAACUCAAACCUAGCUACUCCAAUAGCAAUUAAAGCAGUGCCACCCAGUAAAAGGUUCCUUAAACAUGGACAGAACAUCCGAGAUGUCAGCAACAAAGAAAACUGAAAUUCCAGUGGAUCUAUCCAACACAGAAACUGAACAAAAUGAGAUGAAAGCCGAGCUGGACCGAUUUUAACAUUCACAUUGCCCUGCCUCUGUCCCCCUUUAAACGUUGACCCAUUUUAAAGACAAACAUGAACAUUAACAUCAUAAUAUGCUUUUUAUGAAGUUUCAAUAAGGUUUAACCUUAGUCUUGUUGACAUGUAGCCCAGUCAUUCACUCUUUAAGGAUUAUUAGUGUUUCAUUGAUACUAAAUUACCCAGCUUAAUCAACAGAAUGGUUUAAGUAGUACCAGGAAGUAGGACAAGUAAUUUCAAAAAUAUAAAGGUGUUUGCUACUCAGAUGAGGCCGCCCCUGACCUUCUGGCCAGAGAGACAUUGCUGCCAGCCAGCUCUGCCUUCCCAUCAUCUCCUUUCAGGACCGUCCCACACCUUUUACUUGCUCAGUGCUGUCUGAAGAUGCAGUUGCUGUUUGCAAACAACAGGAACACCAGUUAAACUAAUUAGGAAAAGAGGGAGAUUUCCAGGCCUGGGUAACUAUAUACUGUGACCAUUGGAGGUAGAGACAGGUCUCAACAGUUGGAACCAGGAACUCUGCUGUCAGGUUGAGAGUUUUGUUUCUCUUCCAGCUUUUCACUGUGUGGGGGUCUUUUCUCUUAUGUCAGCUCUUUCUAUCACAUGGCAGCUGACCUCUCACGCUCCACUCUGCAGCUUGGACACCCAGUAGACCCUGAAUUUCACUCUCUCUAAAAGGUUCUGAGGGCUCAUCCUGGGCCAGGGGCCCUCCUGUGCACUGUUAGCUAUGGCCACGGGAGCCUCCAGAGCUGCCUGGUAGCUUCAGGUUGACCUGCUUAUCAGGCCUACGAUCCUUCUGAUUUAAGUACAGCUGGAAAGUAUUAUCUAAUUAAGUUCAUGAUAGUGCUUUUGGAGAACUUGUCAAAUUACAGCCAAUGAGAAAAUAAGGACCUAGCAUACUGUGGAGAACCAUUAAAAAUUUGAGAAGAAACAACAAGUAUUAUGUCAACUUACUUCAAAGGCGUAGUUUUGGGAAUUUGAUGCAGUAAAGAUUACCCUGUUUUAUGAUUGUUCCUUGAAAGUCAAAUGGGGGACCUGUCCAUUGUGCUCUAUUAAUCUUGUCAGAAAACUGUCACCAAAACAAAACUUGAGUUUGUCCUUGUUCUAGGAGUUACUGGGUAGUUGUAAGUAUUAUUUUUAUUAAAUAUAAUGUAAAAUAAAAUGUUAAGAUACUUAGUUUUGUUUUUCAAAGUAAAGCUGUAGUCAGCCUUAUGUAUGCCAUUGACUCUGAAAUGUAUACCAGCCUUUCACUGUGUACCGUGUGUAUAUAAAUCCACAGAACCGGAUGAGCUGCUUAGGGAGGGAAUAUAUUCAAAGUGUACCAAGGACCAAAUCCUGGAGUUCUCCCAACUUUAGAGGAUGGAAAGGGGCAGAGUAAUCUAGCAAAGGAGACUGAGGCCAGUGAAGUAGGAAGAAAGUAUUUCAAGGAGAGUGAUGAUUCUGUGAAUAUUGCUGAGAAUUCAAAUAAAAAGAGGACUGAGAACUGA